CCAUUGGUGAUAUCCUUGACAAAGUAGUUUAGCCCAAGGAGCUUGUCAUGGACCAUGGGCAUGGAGGGUCUUCUCCAGAACUCCACUAACUUCGUCCUCACAGGCCUCAUCACCCAUCCUGCCUUCCCCGGGCUUCUCUUUGCAAUAGUCUUCUCCAUCUUUGUGGUGGCUAUAACAGCCAACUUGGUCAUGAUUCUGCUCAUCCACAUGGACUCCCGCCUCCACACACCCAUGUACUUCUUGCUCAGCCAGCUCUCCAUCAUGGAUACCAUCUACAUCUGUAUCACUGUCCCCAAGAUGCUCCAGGACCUCCUGUCCAAGGACAAGACCAUUUCCUUCCUGGGCUGUGCAGUUCAGAUCUUCCUCUACCUGACCCUGAUUGGAGGGGAAUUCUUCCUGCUGGGUCUCAUGGCCUAUGACCGCUAUGUGGCUGUGUGCAACCCUCUACGGUACCCUCUCCUCAUGAACCGCAGGGUUUGCUUAUUCAUGGUGGUCGGCUCCUGGGUUGGUGGUUCCUUGGAUGGGUUCAUGCUGACUCCUGUCACUAUGAGUUUCCCCUUCUGUAGAUCCCGAGAGAUCAAUCACUUUUUCUGUGAGAUCCCAGCCGUGCUGAAGUUGUCUUGCACAGACACGUCACUCUAUGAGACCCUGAUGUAUGCCUGCAUGCUGCUUAUCCCUCUAUCUGUCAUCUCUGUGUCCUACACGCACAUCCUCCUGACUGUCCACAGGAUGAACUCUGCUGAGGGCCGGCGCAAAGCCUUUGCUACGUGUUCCUCCCACAUUAUGGUGGUGAGCGUUUUCUACGGGGCAGCCUUCUACACCAACGUGCAGCCCCACUCCUACCACACUCCAGAGAAAGAUAAAGUGGUGUCUGCCUUCUACACCAUCCUCACCCCCAUGCUCAACCCACUCAUCUACAGCUUGAGGAAUAAAGAUGUGGCUGCAGCUCUGAGGAAAGUACUAGGGAGAUGUGGCUCCUCCCAGAGCAUCAGGGUGAUGACUGUGAUCAGGAAGGACUAGCAGGGACUCCCAGAGUAUCAGCGUGGUGACUAUGAUCAGGAAGGACUAGUGGGGACUCCUAGAGCAUCAGGGUGGCGACUGUGAUCAGGAAGGACUAGCAAGGACUAGCGCAAACAUCUGCGGUGCUGCGGCCAAUAACGCAGCUAUUACAGAAAAUAUGGUAUUGGUUCUGAAGAAUGUUCAGUGUCACUUUUAGCAAUUCAGAAUUAACAGGCAAAAUCAUCCUGUUGCAAGGAUUACUUAGGAACAGUAGCGAGGUUGGUGAGGAUCUCUGCAUUAGUCAACUUUGUUCAACUGGAUUCACAAACGUUUCCAGAGGGCAUUCUCAGUCAAGUAGCCCUACAAACCAUGGCACGCCAAGCAGCUCUUGGAAGUGCCCAUGUUAACAUGUGAUCAUGAGUCCUUCCUGUCUGUAUUGCUGACGUGUGAUCAUGAGUCCUGCCUGUCUGUAUUGCUAAUGUGUGAUCAUGAGUCCUGCCUGUCUGUAUUGCUGACGUGUGAUCAUGGGUCCUGACUGUAUUGCUGACCAACUUUUGAAUGGAAAUUGGAGCAUUUGCCACCUCCUUGAUGACUUAAUUUCAAACAUUCAAUACAAGUAAAAUAUUUUCUAGUGACAAAUGUGUAGCAAUUUUAUUUAGAAAAUAUUUAGGAAGGUGAUACUAUUUUUGGUUCCAUAUUCUUAGUUACAUUUUAUGAAUGUUAUCACUUACCUCUGAAAUUAAAUACUUGCCCUGCCUUUAUUCACAUGGAGUCCAAUAUAUUCCUGGAAAUAUUGAUUCAUUGAUUGAAAAUUGACUCUGCCAUUAAGAUUGUUACAUGGCCAAAAACCUACAAAACUGCCAUUUAUGCUCAAAUUGUUAAUAUAUAAAUGUAGAAUGAAUAAACCAAGACAUUUUAUUAGCUAACUUAGUUCCCGUGGAAUAAGUUGCUCAAUUUUCUUAUUCUCAACAUCUUCAUUGAUAUGCUGAAGACAAGUAUUUUUGUAAUUAGUUGGAGUUAGGUGUGGUGCUUUGAUAGAUGUGUAACUUUGGUGGAAUACUAACUAAGCAAAGACUACACUGACCCCACGAUUCAUGUAACUUUAGUUUCUCCUGUGUGUAAGGUCCUGAAAUAUGAGACAUAAAAAAUAUUGACGGGACCUGGUGUUUAUUUUGUUGAUACGAGGCUUAGAAAACAUUGGACAGAGCGGUUACAUAGUUGACAAAGACUAAGCAAACGUUACUCAGCCUUAUGUUGUUCUAGUGUCAACACAGAUAGAAGGAAAAAUGUUUCCUCCAUUGUUGCUGAUGUAGAUAAAGAAUAUUCCCUUCAAUAUGCUAACCCCUAGGUGGCUUUUCAUUCAGAAGGUUCCUAAUAAUUUGAUCUUUACCCUGAAAUCAAACACAUGGAAAAGAGAUGGAAGAAUGUCCUGGAGGGAUUAAGUGAAGAAACAGACCAGGAUUCAUUUAUGAAAUAUCCUCGGUGUUAUUUCAAUUCAGCUCCAUUCACAUUUUAUUCCUUUGUGUGUCUGCACUAAUGCCCUCCAUAUUCUCCAUUCUCCUGCCUUAGCUAGCACCUUCUCGAUCUUCCCUCUACAAAACUCCUUCAGUUCACGUUGUAUUUGUGCUCUAUCCUGGGAUAUCUGUGUUUUCUUUCCCAUUUCCUCAGUUGCUAUGUAUUAAAAAUUAG